AUGGAAUCCACUAAGAAGGGGCGAGACCAGUGAGGAUUCAACUAAAGGGAGCGAGAAGGGGCGGGGACCCGGGAGGAGGAAGUGGAGUGGCCACCGAGGAAGAGGGGAGUGGUCGGGGUGGGGCACAGGAUGGUGGAGAGACUGUCAACAACUUUUAAUGAGCUCCCUUGGCGUCCUAGCCUAGCCCCCAGGCACUGGGAGCAUUGCAGAAAGAGAAAGAUACUGUCCCUGUCCUCUAGGUGUUUCCAGUCUAGUUGGGGAGACAAAACAAAUACACAUUAAAUAGAUAACAAACAACUCCAACUUGUAAGGCUAUAAUAGAUACGUGUAGAGCAUAUGUAUAAUGCACUGUAUUCAGGAAUUCCAAGCAGUUCGAACGUCAUGACCCCUCAGAAGUUGACCCAGAAGCUGGUGAAGGAGGCCCAGAGAAAGAUACAGGGUGAGGCACAGUGAAUCUGCUGGACCAGCUUCAAGAACAAUAUGUCAGCCUAUCCACUGCCACCUCCCACAGCUCCAGACUCGUGGGUGCUUCCUGGAUGUGACCAGCCAUAGAAUUUAUCACCCUGGCAAGGACCCUGGUACUUGGAAGCUUGGAGAAAGUGAUUCAGGGCUCUUACCCGCAGUGGGCAGGACUGCUGACGGCUCCCAGCUGGAUUUUCCUGCAACUGCCCUCAAUGAAGCAAGCUGUUCCACCCAAGGUUGAUGCAGGACAAAGAGGGUCUCGCUCUGUCGCCCAGGCUGGAGUGCAGUGGCGAGUCACUACAGCCUCGACCUCUCCGGCUCAAGCCAUCCUCCCGUCUCUGUCUCCCAAAGUGCUGGGAUUACAGCGGUGAGCCACUGUGCCUGGCUUACUGCCUCAUCUUGUUCCCUGAGGUUCUAGACCUCUAGGGUGUUGUCCGGAAAGAACAGGGCCAUGUGGAAGUCAGCAAAGAGAGAGGCCGAUUGAACAGCAGGCUCUUCUCAGGCAUCGCCAAGUGACUGAUUAGGAUUGGCCACCAGGGGGUGCCAUGGAGCCACAGUCUAUGAAGGGACAGAAGAGGCCUUUUGGGGGACCCUGGAGGUUGAAGGUGCUGGGAGGCCCUCCUUGGCUUAGGAGGACACUUCCAAAGCUGGGGCGCCCCAAGGAGGCACCAGUGGCCAGAAUGUCCACGCAGAGCACCCACCCCCUGAAACCUGAGGCCCCACGUCUGCCACCUGGGAUCCCCGAGUCCCCGAGCUGUCAGCGGCGCCACACACUCCCUGCCAGUGAGUUUCGCUGCCUCACCCCGGAGGACGCUGUCAGCGCCUUUGAGAUCGAGCGUGAAGCCUUCAUCUCCGUCUUGGGCGUCUGCCCCCUGUACCUGGAUGAGAUCCGGCACUUCCUGACCCUAUGUCCAGAGCUGUCCCUGGGCUGGUUCGAGGAGGGCUGCCUUGUGGCCUUCAUCAUCGGCUCGCUCUGGGACAAGGAGAGACUCAUGCAGGAGUCACUGACGCUGCACAGGUCUGGGGGCCACAUAGCCCACCUGCAUGUGCUGGCCGUGCACCGCGCCUUCCGGCAGCAGGGCAGGGGCCCCAUCCUGCUGUGGCGCUACCUGCACCACCUGGGCAGCCAGCCGGCCGUGCGCCGGGCCGCGCUCAUGUGCGAGGACGCGCUGGUACCCUUCUAUGAGAGGUUCAGCUUCCACGCCGUGGGCCCCUGCGCCAUCACCGUGGGCUCCCUCACCUUCAUGGAGCUCCACUGCUCCCUGCGGGGCCACCCCUUCCUGCGCAGGAACAGCGGCUGCUGAACUGGGCUGCCCACCUGGCUGCCAACAUGAUCCCCGUCUCUGCCCUGGGCUCCUCUUAGCUCAGCUGAGCAUGGAGACAGCAGUUUCCAGAGAGUGGAGAGAGCAGGGCUAAAUAAAGAGGAGAUAAGGUGGCUUCUCACGGCCUGA